AGUAGGGAGGAAAACCGGAGGAGAGCGCAGGAGGAAACAGUACCGGCUGGAGGCCGGUCUUGCAGGAGCGGGGGACUGCUGGGGGCGGGGCUUGGUGGUGACCGCUGGCGGGGCGGGGCCUGGGGCUCAGAGGGGUGGGCUUUGGAGAUCAGAGGGUCGACGCUGCUUCGUUGCCUGGACUCUGGUUUCCGCCCUGGAGCAAGCCGGGGCCUGGUCGGCAGCUGGGCCGCCAUGGAGUCCACGCUGGGCGCGGGCAUCGUGAUAGCCGAGGCGCUACAGAACCAGCUAGCCUGGCUGGAGAACGUGUGGCUCUGGAUCACCUUUCUGGGCGAUCCCAAGAUCCUCUUUCUGUUCUACUUCCCCGCGGCCUACUACGCCUCCCGCCGUGUGGGCAUCGCGGUGCUCUGGAUCAGCCUCAUCACCGAGUGGCUCAACCUCAUCUUCAAGUGGUGAGACAGAGAAGCCCUCCGGCAUCCUGGUCCCCACCCCCGAGGGCCCUGAGUCAUGUAAGCAUGCUUUGUGCUGGGCAUCACGGUAGCUGCUAAGGACAGAGACACCUUGCAGAUUAAGGUGUGGUCCCUGGACCAUGCCCAACGGCAUAGGCAGCACUUGAAAACUGGCUAAAAACGCAGACUCUCAGGCCCCGGGCCAGAGCUACUGAAUCAAAAUCUGCAUUUUAACAAGGUUCCCAGGUUUCUUUUUGGAGACAGGCCCUUUUGGUGGGUCCAUGAGUCUGGUUACUACAGCCAGGCUCCAGCCCAGGUUCACCAGUUCCCCUCUUCUUGUGAGACUGGUCCAGGCAGCCCUUCUGGACACUGCAUGAUCACAGGAGCAGCCCUCUGGCCCAUAAUGACGGCCCUGUCUUCGCAGGUGGCCACUCGGGCCCGCAGCCGCUGGGUAAGGGUGAUGCCUAGCCUGGCUUAUUGCACCUUCCUUUUGGCGGUUGGCUUGUCGCGAAUCUUCAUCUUAGCACAUUUCCCUCACCAGGUGCUGGCUGGCCUAAUAACUGGCGCUGUCCUGGGCUGGCUGAUGACUCCCCGAGUGCCUAUGGAGCGGGAGCUAAGCUUCUAUGGGUUGACUGCACUGGCCCUCAUGCUAGGCACCAGCCUCAUCUAUUGGACCCUCUUUACACUGGGCCUGGAUCUUUCUUGGUCCAUCAGCCUAGCCUUCAAGUGGUGUGAGCGGCCUGAGUGGAUACACGUGGAUAGCCGGCCCUUUGCCUCCCUGAGCCGUGACUCAGGGGCUGCCCUGGGCCUGGGCAUUGCCUUGCACUCUCCCUGCUAUGCCCAGGUGCGUCGGGCACAGCUGGGAAAUGGCCAGAAGAUAGCCUGCCUUGUGCUGGCCAUGGGGCUGCUGGGCCCCCUGGACUGGCUGGGCCACCCCCCUCAGAUCAGCCUCUUCUACAUUUUCAAUUUCCUCAAGUACACCCUCUGGCCAUGCCUAGUCCUGGCCCUCGUGCCCUGGGCAGUGCACAUGUUCAGUGCCCAGGAAGCACCGCCCAUCCACUCUUCCUGACUUCUUGUGUGCCUCCCUUUCCUUUCCCUCCCACAAAGCCAACACUCUGUGACCACCACACUCCAGGAGGCAGCCCCAUCCCCUUCCAGCCCCUAAGUAGGCCCUCCCCUCCCUAAAUCUGCUUCCGCACCACCUGGUCUUAGCCCCAAAGAUGGGCCUUCUCUCUCCCAGAUAAGUUGGUCCUCCCUCUGCCUUUCCUCUCAAGCCCCCAAAGAGCAAAGGCAACAGCAAGACCAGCGGGUUCUUGCAACACUGUGAGGGGCAGCCAGGGCGGCCCCAAUAAAGCCCUUGAAUACUUUGA